AACUGAAGUUCAGCCACCUGCCACUCCUGACUGCAUGGAAGCCAGGUGCAAGGAGAAAGGAUUUUGAGGAGGGGACUCCAUGGCUUCCGAGUUGCUGACUGACCCUCCACCUCAGAGGUAGUUCUGACACUGUCUCAGUUUUGCAGAUGAAGAUGAGAUUCUUCAGUUCUCCAUGUGGAAAAGCAGCUGUGGACCCAGCCGCAGCCGCCGUGCUCAGCGCGAGCCCCGGAGCCCUUGAGCGCGAGGCGCGGAGCCCCCGGAGCCCCCAAACCGCAGACACAUCCCCGCGCCCCAGAGCCCCGGCCUGCGCGCCCAGCCGGGCCCGCGCGAUGCCCUCAGACCGGCCUUUCAAGCAGCGGCGGAGCUUCGCCGACCGCUGUAAGGAGGUACAGCAGAUCCGCGACCAGCACCCCAGCAAAAUCCCGGUGAUCAUCGAGCGCUACAAGGGUGAGAAGCAGCUGCCCGUCCUGGACAAGACCAAGUUUUUGGUCCCGGACCAUGUCAACAUGAGCGAGUUGGUCAAGAUCAUCCGGCGCCGCCUGCAGCUGAACCCCACGCAGGCCUUCUUCCUGCUGGUGAACCAGCACAGCAUGGUGAGUGUGUCCACGCCCAUCGCGGACAUCUACGAGCAGGAGAAAGACGAGGACGGCUUCCUCUAUAUGGUCUACGCCUCCCAGGAAACCUUCGGCUUCUGAGCCAGCAGUAGGGGGGCUCGGCCUGGGAGUCGGGCGGCCCCGGUCAGGCCCUGCCCAGAGAGCUCCUGGUUCCUGAACUGAGCUGCCUCUACCGUGGUGGGCUGGGCAGGCAUGUGCCCCCCUAGUCAGAGGGCACCAACCCACCUACUCUGCCCCUGGGUGGAUCCUGGGCCGGUCGUGUUAGGGUUGUCCCUCUGGGUGCUGGCUGGUGGGAUGGGGGAGGGUGGGGAGCAGCUCCCAGCACCCCUGCUGUGUGGUUCAUCUUUUUUUUAGGCCCCUGCCUGUCUGCCCAUCUGCCCCUCACCCACCCGAGGCUCUGCCCACCGCCUGGACCUGCCCACCCCUGAAAGACUGGCCCCUGGCUCCCCGCCCCUCGGUCUCCACGUGGUGUAUGGAUCUGUGGUCAUUGUCCCUCUGCAGAAUAAAGAUUGCUCAGGCCUGCCUGGC